GACUGCGGGAGUGGAGCCGGCGAGAGAGUGGCAGCGGGGGCUGAUGGAAGUGCAGUGGGGGCUGGAGAGGGCACCCUACUGUAUCCAGCAUGCUCCAAGGCCACAGCUCUGUGUUCCAGGCCUUGCUGGGGACCUUCUUCACCUGGGGGAUGACAGCAGCUGGGGCAGCUCUCGUGUUCGUAUUCUCUAGUGGACAGAGGCGGAUCUUAGAUGGAAGUCUUGGCUUUGCUGCAGGGGUCAUGUUGGCAGCUUCCUAUUGGUCUCUUCUGGCCCCAGCAGUUGAGAUGGCCACGUCCUCUGGGGGCUUCGGUGCCUUUGCCUUCUUCCCUGUGGCUGUUGGCUUCACCCUUGGAGCGGCUUUUGUCUACUUGGCUGACCUCCUGAUGCCUCACUUGGGUGCAGCAGAAGACCCCCAGACGACCCUGGCACUGAACUUCGGCUCUACGUUGAUGAAGAAGAAGUCUGAUCCUGAGGGUCCCGCGCUGCUCUUCCCUGAGAGUGAACUUUCCAUCCGGAUAGGUAGAGCUGGGCUUCUUUCAGACAAGAGUGAGAAUGGUGAGGCAUAUCAGAGAAAGAAGGCGGCAGCCACUGGCCUUCCAGAGGGUCCUGCUGUCCCUGUGCCUUCUCGAGGGAAUCUGGCACAGCCCGGCGGCAGCAGCUGGAGGAGGAUCGCACUGCUCAUCUUGGCCAUCACUAUACACAACGUUCCAGGAGAAUGAGGGUGGGAAGAAAGAGCAAAAGAAACAGCAAAGAGAUUAGAAAAACAACAACAACAGAACUCUCUGAUUCACCAAUGAUCAAAGCUGUGUCUGGAAGUUCAUUGCUGUUACAGCAUCCUGUUCUCCCCAACAUGUAGGGAUUCCUAAGUUCAAGUCCCAUCUGAAGAAUAUAGUCAUGGAGCUGAAAGGACACUCUACAACUGGGCAACCACCUUCAGGAACUUUCCUCAGCCUACAGAAAUAAGGACAGAUGAUUUAGAAUGAAGCACAUAGGACUUUGAAAACCAAGUUCAACUCUCCGCAAUGGAUUCUGGCUUCUGAGUUAGGAUAAGGGAUUGGCUGCAUGUAUAGAAUAUCUGAAACAAUGUUAUCUUUUCUCAUAUAAAGGAAAGCUAGAGACAGGCAUUCCAGCACAGGUACAACAACAACAAAACACUUUUAGGGACAUCAGACUUUUUGAGACACAGUUUUACUCUGUUGCUCAGGCUGGAGUGCAAUGGCCCAAUCUCGGCUCACUGCAGCCUCCACCUCCCAGGUUCAAGCGAUUCUCCUGCCUCAUCUCCCAAGUAGCUGGAACUGCAGGUGGCCACUACCACAUCUGGCUAAUUUUUGUAUUUUUAGUAGAGGCAGGGUUUCGCCAUGUUGGCCAGACUGGUCUCAAACUCCUGAUCUCAAGUGAUCUGCCUGCCUUGGCCUCCCAAAGUGCUGGGAUUAUAGGUGUGAGCCACCACACCUGGCCCUAGGACAUAAAUCUUUUUUUUGAGACAGAGUUUCGCUCUUGUUGCCCAGGCUGGAGUGCAGUGGUGUGAUCUCGGCUCACUGCAACCUCCACCUCCUGGGUUCAAGUGAUUCUCCUGUCUCAGCCUCCCAAGUAGCUGGGAUUACAGGCACCUGCCACCAUGACCUGCUAAUUUUGUAUUUUUAGUAGAGACAGGGUUUCUCCAUAUUGGUCAUGCCGGUCUCUAACUCCUGACCUCGUGAUCCACCUGCCUUGGCCUCCCAAAGUGCUGGGAUUACAGGCAUGAGCCACCACGCCCAGCCUCUCCUGCAUUCUUUCUGGAGCUUUCCGAGUCUGUAGGGUGAAAUCAUAACAGCUUGAUUUUCUCAUAUCAAUGUCUUCCUAACCUGUUCUGUUGGCUCUCCCUUCCCUUCCCCUGGGUGAUUCCAUAGACAGCUACAUUUUCCUGUAAGUUUUAGGUAUUGAUGAGCAGAUUCAUUGUCAUAUGCAAUCCCGAUGGACCAGUCUUAAUAGAACUUCAGCAUCUCCUUGAGUAGAGCAUUCUUUCCUUCCACCAAUAACUCCUGGGUUGCUUUAGCCUUGGCAGCCUGCAGUGGACAAGAUGUGGGUGGUUUGCCCCUUCCUUAGUUUUUUACCCCCUACCCUGCUUGCCUUGCCAAUUCCUUAGGAUUGAAGGAAGAAAGAAGUGAAGGAUUGUGUUUGGGUGGUGAGUGACAAAAGGCCUUCCCUAAAGGUUACAGUUAUAAUUUAGUGUUGGUGUCCUUGAAGUAGCAGAUUCUCAAGUGUGGACCAUUGUUCUCAUGGGGUCCUAAUUGUGAGGGCUCUUCAGAGCCUCUUCAUGGAAAUAUACACAGGGAUGGGCAGGAUGCAUUGUGGAUGACCUCUUGGGGUCCCCCCAGCCCCAGGUGAUCCUCUCUGCACAGAUGCUAUUAGAAUCAGUUUGUCCUUGCAGGCUGAUCUCUCGGGUUAACCUUUAUAGCUUGUUUGUACCUAGUCACCUUCUAAAAUGUCACCUUGGCCCUUUGCCUCUGGAAAUGCAGGCUGCUUCCAGGGCAUCCCCCUCUCCUCUGAUGGCUACUGGAGUUCUCUCAGGCACCUUCUCACCUCGGGACUAUUCCACAAUGUGUUCAGAGCCCAGUUCUCCAGAGGAGCAUGCCAAACUCUGCAAGCAUGUCUCUUGCAGUGGCCCUCAUUUGGCCUGAGUAUAGAGGAACUCCUCCAUCCUCAGGGUGAGCUCUGACAACUCUCCAAGGCCGUUCUUGGUAUGGUCGUUCUUGUCUCUCCGCCUUCCAUGGGACCACUGGGGGCCGAGGGCACCAUUUGGGAGGAACUACUCCUUCUCCAGUUCUGCAAGAGGGUCAGGUACUUCUCAGUAGAGUAACACUGUCCUGUAGAACUUUCUGCAGUGAUAGAAAUACUCAGUAUCUGCACGGUCCAGUAUGGUAGCCAUGAAUCCCCUGGGGCUUUUGAGUACUUGAAAGGUGGCUGCUAUGACUGAGGAAAUGGUGUGUAAUCUUGUUUAAUUAAUUUAAGUGUAAAAAGCCGCAUGUGGCUACUGUAUUAGACAUGCCGUGUUGUUCUAGAAUGUAGAAUGAGAGGGUAAUGUCAACAGUUUUUCUCAGCAACAGUUCUGAGACCGGAUAAGUCCCAUUAUAUAUCUUGCUCAGCUCUCUCAAGAAAGCGGUUCUCAUGGCCUCCUAACCCAUCAGUGAGUAGCGCUGUCAGUGUCACGUUUUAAAUGUUGCUUCACAAAAGCACUCUUACGGAGGUAGACUCUAGCCUUCAUUAGUGGAAUAUGCAGGUCCUUCUCUGCCGCCUCCCUCUGCCCCAUCCUGCCUUAACUAAAGGCGUUUUACUCUUUUGAGGGUAAUAUUUGAAGUCUUAGCUCCUGGCGUACUUUUGUACCACCUGCUAAAAAGCUCAUUGCUUUCCUGGCAGAAGUGCCCCUGGCAGUGCUAUGAUGGGCUUUUGGCUGAGAGGCAGAGUGAUCAACUUCUGCUUUUCUCUCCGGAGAACACUUGGUAGAUUGGAUGCUGCCAAGAGUUCCACAGCAUUCUGAUGAUGACAUCCAUGAUUAUAGAGGAGGAUAGAACUAGUCCCAGGGUCUGAUCCAUGAAUGUAUUUGCCCUUAGUUCAGGCUCAGCUUCAUAAAGAACCAUGGUAUUUUACCAGGUUAAUCAAGUACAGUCUAAGGUAGCAGAAAAUUAAUAUUAUGCUUUAGAAUGUGCAGUAGCUCUGCUUAUUCUAAUUAGAGAAAAUGGGUGUCUUAAUUAGACAAAAAUAUCGAAAUUUUUAGAGCACUUUAAACAAAUUCGGUUUUAUUACUUCAAAAUACAAAUUAAAAUCUGACAAUGGGGACCAGAAAAGAGUUCUCCAUCCGUUAGGGUUUGUUGGUUGUGAGCAACAGAUGUCAUCUCUGGCCAGCUAAAGCAUAUGAAGAAGUUUUUCAAAAGUAUAAGGAGUAACUCAGAGAAUCUAAGGAAAAGCUAGUCUUUGGAAGACCAAUAGCAAGGCAUCCCAAAACCUGCAAUAAUAGACGGGAGCUAUGGGCAGUCUCUUCAAAGAGCUGACGUCAGAAUGACUCACGAACAACCAUUUUCUGCCCCUGUGUCAUUCAGCUCAACUUUCAAUUCUGGAAGAGAAAAUCGGAUUGGGAGAAUCCAGGUCAGGUUGUAGAGGCCAACACUAAGGGGCGGGGAGGAGCUUGUUCAUCGGACUGUGUAGGAUGGAGGCAGGGAAUUUCUCAAAGAAAAGCGGGAUGCUAUCACCAAAAGAAGCAGUAAGGAUGCUGAGCUUAUGAAAACUAAACCCCCCCAAGCACAAUGCCUUCUUAAAUGACAUCGAGAUAUUUAUACACAAGAGGGAGUUACAAGAACGAACUUGCUAUUUAUUUGUCAUUGUAGUUUUCAUCCAUAUAUCAUAGAAUGUUAAAGUUCACCGUAAAAAGACGACUUUGGAAAUUAUUCAGUUUACCCUAGUAUGUGCACUUUUCAAAUCAAGAAACUGGAUGUCUUGUCCAAGGCUGGGUAAUAGCAGAGGUGGGACCAGAAGCAGAUGUUUUGACUGUGAUAUGAGGCCCCGUUGCUAUUCCAUUCUGCCUUGCUCAUCAAGAAUUACUUUUAAGUUGCUUAAAGGCACAUUAUCUUCUUGUGUGGCUAACCAUUUCUUUUGCAAUCUGAAUGAUGCAAUUAAAUUGCCUAGACAUCUUUGUUAUACAUUGUAUCCAA